GGAAACAGCGCGGGGUCCGCUAUGGCGGCGGCAGCCGAGGGCGUACUGGCGACCCGGAGUGAUGAGCCCGCCCGAGAUGGAGAAUGGAGCCGACUUGAUGGAAUGAAGGCAAGUGGAGGGAUGUCGGAACAGGCUGCUUUGGCUGGAUUAGCACCGGGUGUAGGCGGGACACUUAGUCAUUCUCCCUUGGCCCAGACGAUGCCGCCGUGGAGACAGCUGAGGAAGCAAAGGAGCCUGCUGAAGCUGACAUCACUGAGCUCUGCCGGGACAUGUUCUCCAAAAUGGCCACUUACCUGACUGGGGAACUGACGGCCACCAGUGAAGACUAUAAGCUCCUGGAAAAUAUGAAUAAACUCACCAGCUUGAAGUAUCUUGAAAUGAAAGAUAUUGCUAUAAACAUUAGUAGGAACUUAAAGGACUUAAACCAGAAAUAUGCUGGACUGCAGCCUUAUCUGGAUCAGAUCAAUGUCAUUGAAGAGCAGGUAGCAGCUCUUGAGCAGGCAGCUUACAAGUUGGAUGCAUAUUCAAAAAAACUGGAAGCCAAGUACAAGAAGCUGGAGAAGCGAUGAGAAACUUAUUUCUAUGGGACAGAGUCUUUUUUUUUUAAUGUGGAAGAAUGUCUUAUAAAACCUGAAUCCUGAGGCUGAUGAAUUGUGAAAAUUCCUCAAAAGGAAAUUAUGCUGGUCAUCACAGGAACAUCUCAACGUUCGAGUAAACUGGAGGACUGUGGCUAUUCCUGAACCUUCUUUGAGACAGAAUCCCUCAGAAUCUCACACUUAUAACUUCCUACCUUUUACUUGAAUGCUUUGCCAUAUUCAGGACAGAGACUCUCACAAAGUUCAGAAAACAGCUGGACUUACCAGUAAAAUCAAAUGAGAGGACCUAUUUUCUCUGGUAGUGGUUGAUUACUACAUUAUUUUCUUAAGUGGCUGGUUUUUUAGUUACUAUGUAAAUGGUCGUUUUUCUGUUAAUGAUGCUAAUGUGUUGUAAACAAGAUUCUAAAUUUAAAAAGGAAAACAAAACAAACUUGUUCUUUGCAGCUUAUCACCUUGUGAAUGUCGGUAACUUACUUUUCCAUAAUAUUGCAAAUAACAUAAAAUCUUAAAAUAAUUCCAAGCUGAGUCUUCUAGAUUGAGCAGAAAUGGUGAAAGGAGUAUUGAUAACUUGGCGUAUGUGAUGGGCCCCUCUUGUUUAUUUUCUAUGUGAGUCACAUUGACAUGCGAUCAGUUUGGGAAAUGUGAUGAAAACAAAGACUAGAUGGGUAUGUGUGUUUAUGUGUUGGGUAGGGAGGUGACGAUUGCCACUCAUAAAAUAAAGGAUUUUAUAAAAUACCUUCCUACUGUGUAUGUAGGAUUUGGGGGGAUCUUAGGGACCUAAUCGACUUCUUUGCACACUAAAAACAUCAGACAAUGGGACAUACUGACUGACCAGUCUAGGUUGAAAGAUAGGCAGCCUUACCCAGAACACAACAUUAGCAGCUGGGAAGGUGUCUGAGGUCCCCAAUUACAUAUCCCAAAGAGUUUCUUACUUCUGUUUCUGUCAUUUCCCCUCUGUUCCAGACAGUCAUCAUUUAUCCUCUGUUCUUCCUGGACUGUUGCUGUGGUCUCUUCUCAUCUUAACUGUCCCUUCCAACCACCCUCCACACUGCUGCCAGAGCAAUCUUAAAAAUGUAAACUGGCCCUAUUACUCCUGCUUAGAACCCUGUAGUGACUUAUCAUGGCCUCUGAAAAAUCUAGACUUUCAUUAUGCAUACAAGUCCCUUGUGUUUUUUUGUUUGUUUAUAGACAGGGUCUCUAUUGUCACCCAGGCUGGAGUGUGGUGGUGUGAUAAUAGCUCACCUUGACCUCCUAGGCUCAACUGAUCUUCCCACCUCAGCCUCCUGAAUAGCUGGGACUACCAGCACGCUCCACCAUGCCUUGCUAAUUAUUUUUUAUACAGAUGGAGUCUCACUAUGUUGUCCAGGCUGGUCUUGAACUGGCCUCAAGUGAUUCUCUUACCACAGCCUGCCAGAGUGCUGAGAUUGUAGGCAUGAACCACCGUGCCUAACAUAAGGCCCCUAUUUAAACAUUUUUCUUAAAUAAAAAACAAAAGAAUUAAACUGUAACUCUACUAUCUUAACAUAGAAUCAGUCUUACCCCUUCUUCCAACCCUUUUCCUUUUCCGUGCAUGUAUUGAUCUAUUUUUUUUUUUUUUUUGAGAUGAAGUCUUGCUCUGUCGCCUGGGCUGGAGUGCAGUGGUGCGAUCUUAGCUCACUGCAACCUCUGUUUCCUGGGUUCAAGCGAUUCUCCUGCCUCAGCCUCCCGAGUAGUUGAGAUUUACAGGUGCCCACCACCAUGCCAGGCUAAUUUUUGUAUUUUUAGUAGAGACGGGGUUUCACCAUGUUGGCCAGGCUGGUCUCGAACUCCUGACCCCAAAUGAUCCACCCACCUCGGCCUCCCAAAGUGCUGGGAUUACAGGUGUGAGCCACCGCACCCAGCCAUGUUGAUCUAUUUUUAAAAAGUUUUUAUUUCCUGUUACACUGUGUUCAGCUAUCUUCAGCCACCUUAAAUUCCCAUGGAUGAGUUUUCAUAAACUUUUUGAAAAUAGAUUUAGAUUUACGGGAAAGUUGCAAAGAUAAUACAGAAUUUAAUGGAUGAGUUUUUUUAUUGAUGUGUAAUAGAUGUAUGUAUUUUCAGAGUACAAGUGAUAAUUUAAUACAUGUAUAUAAUGUGUAAAUAUUAAAUCAAGAGUUAUUGGGA